AGACACAUUUGGGUGCCGGGAGAGUGAGGCCGCGGGGGCUGGGAAGGGACCGGUGUAUGGGGGACAGCAGGCGAAGGUCACUCGGGAACCAGCCCAGCUCUGAGGCUGCGGGCAGGUCGGAAAGGGAGCAGGACGGCGACCCCCGUGGCCUCCAGAGCUCUGUGUACGAGAGCCGGCGGGUCACAGACCCCGAACGCCAGGACCUGGACAAUGCAGAGCUGGGACCAGAAGACCCAGAAGAGGAGCUUCCCCCCGAGGAGGUGGCCGGGGAGGAGUUCCCGGAGACCCUGGAUCCCAAAGAGGCACUUUCUGAGUUGGAGAGAGUCCUGGACAAGGACUUGGAAGAGGACAUUCCUGAAAUCAGCCGGCUGUCCAUCAGCCAGAAGCUCCCCAGCACCACCAUGACCAAAGCAAGGAAGAGGAGGAGGCGGAGGAGGCUCAUGGAGCUGGCAGAGCCCAAGAUAAACUGGCAAGUCCUGAAAGACAGGAAGGGACGCUGUGGUAAGGGGUAUGCCUGGAUCUCCCCAUGUAAGAUGAGCUUGCACUUCUGUCUCUGCUGGCCCUCUGUGUACUGGACCGAGCGGUUCCUUGAGGACACCACCCUCACCAUCACAGUGCCCGCGGUGUCCCGCCGCGUGGAGGAACUGUCUCGGCCCAAGAGAUUCUACCUGGAAUAUUACAACAACAACAGGACGACUCCUGUCUGGCCCAUUCCUCGGUCCUCCCUGGAAUACAGAGCGUCGAGUCGCCUGAAGGAACUGGCCGCCCCGAAGAUUCGUGAUAACUUCUGGAGCAUGCCCAUGUCUGAGGUGUCCCAGGUAUCCAGGGCAGCCCAAAUGGCAGUCCCCAGCUCGCGGAUCCUCCAGUUGUCAAAGCCGAAGGCCCCAGCCACCCUCUUGGAAGAGUGGGACCCCGUGCCAAAACCCAAGCCACAUGUGUCAGACCAUAACCGCCUCCUUCACUUGGCCAGAGCCUCUUCACAGAGCCAGGGCUGGUCUGCCAAGAAGUGGGUAGCCCUUAUUCAUUUGCGCAGAAGUUCCACGCAAAGAGGGAUCUGGAAAGAAGGGCCCAAAGCUCAGUCGGACAAGUGCGUUCCUGACCGAGAUCCUCGCUGGGAGGUGCUGGAUGUCACCAAGAAGGUGGUGGCCAGCCCCCGGAUCAUCUCCCUGGCCAAGCCCAAAGUGCGCAAGGGCCUCAACGAGGGAUACGACAGGCGUCCCCUCGCCUCUAUGAGCUUGCCACCCCCAAAAGCAUCACCAGAAAAGUGUGAUCAACCCAGGCCUGGCCUCUAAGACCUCCGCUCCCAGUAAACACCCUCAGGCACCCUAACCCUGUGUAUGUGAUUAUUCUGAGCUUUUUGGCCUGGAGAAGGGAGGGCGGGCUAGAAGGCCAAAAGAAGGAUGAGGAGGACAAUAAUAUUUAUUUUUGCAUCCAACCUGCGACUUGUCCAGCUGUUUAUUUUCCGAGUCACUUUCAUUGACCAUCUCGAGCGCCUUCUGAAUCUCUUCAGUCCAGACUUAUUCGUCCAUUCCUGAGGGCCCACGGGACCGUCGGAGUCGGAACGACAGCCACAGUCAAACCAGCCGACGCUCCUGCUGAGGGGCCACGGGACCGUCGGAGUCGGAACGACAGCCACAGUCAAACCAGCCGACGCUCCUGCUGAGGGGCCACGGGACCGUCGGAGUCGGAACGACAGCCACAGUCAAAGCAGCCGACGCUCCUGCUGAGGGCCCACGGGACCGUCG